GAGAGGGGGGUAAGAGACAGUGAGUGCCCAAACACAGCGUCCUGUACAGACAGCUUGGGCGUUGUUCUCAGGGAAGACUGCGCCUCGAAGAUCCUUGGAGGAAACCAAAGUGGGCUCCCAGCCAGGUUCGCUGCUUCUGUCUCUGUCUCUGUCUCGUUAUUCUCACCGCUCCAGCCAUUAAGGAAGAGCACACCGGACCCGAAGGAUGCAGCAUGUGACAGAAUCUCCUUCCUCGAUAAGGCUGAAUGACAUUCCACCGGAGGUAUAGACCACAUUUGGUUGAUCCAUUCACCCAUCAGUGGACACUUGGGCUGCUUCCACCUCUCGGCUAUUGUGCAUAGUGCUGCUAUGUACGUGGGGGCAGUGCUUCAGUCGGGGUGGAGCUGCUUAAAAGGCCUGGGAUCACACCCUUUGGGAACACAUCCAAGCUUAAGACGGUGAGGUCAGCUUCACAUUCUCAGGAACUCUCCUUCUUUGGGCCACGGAAUUAACCCGAGCAGGCAUGGAGGCCUCUGCUCUCACCUCAUCAGCAGUGACCAGUGUGGCCAAAGUGGUCAGGGUGGCCUCUGGCUCUGCCGUAGUUUUGCCCCUGGCCAGGAUUGCUACAGUUGUGAUUGGAGGAGUUGUGGCCAUGGCGGCUGUGCCCAUGGUGCUCAGUGCCAUGGGCUUCACUGCGGCGGGAAUCGCCUCGUCCUCCAUAGCAGCCAAGAUGAUGUCCGCGGCGGCCAUUGCCAAUGGGGGUGGAGUUGCCUCGGGCAGCCUUGUGGCUACUCUGCAGUCACUGGGAGCAACUGGACUCUCCGGAUUGACCAAGUUCAUCCUGGGCUCCAUUGGGUCUGCCAUUGCGGCUGUCAUUGCGAGGUUCUACUAGCUCCCUGCCCCUCGCCCUGCAGAGAAGAGAACCAUGCCAGGGGAGAAGGCACCCAGCCAUCCUGACCCAGCGAGGAGCCAACUAUCCCAAAUAUACCUGGGGUGAAAUAUACCAAAUUCUGCAUCUCCAGAGGAAAAUAAGAAAUAAAGAUGAAUUGUUGCAA